GCAAUCCGGAGUGCCCAACAUGGCGGCGGCCGUAAGGUGCAUGGGUAGAGGUAAGGCGAGGGGUUGUCUUGCAGGGGAAAUGGCUCUGGCACCGAGUCUCUGGUUGCAGCAGAGUGCAAGGCGGAUUCUGCUCUGGGUGCUGAAAAUGCCUCGUGCUGUUUCUGGUCUCUAGGUUUUUCAGAGGCCUUGAUACAUCAUCAAAGGCAUAGCCUUUCCAAGAUGGUUUAUCAGACAUCACUUUGUUCUUGUUCUGUAAACAUCCGAGUGCCCAACAGACAUUUUGCUGCUGCUACAAAGUCUGCAAAGAAAACAAAAAAAGGUGCUAAAGAAAAAACACCAGAUGAGAAAAAAGAUGAAAUAGAAAAAAUAAAAGCAUAUCCCUAUAUGGAAGGCGAACCUGAGGAUGAUGUCUAUUUAAAACGCUUAUACCCGAGACAGAUAUAUGAGGUGGAGAAAGCUGUUCACUUACUUAAGAAAUUUCAAAUUCUUGACUUUACUAGUCCAAAGCAAAGUGUUUAUCUUGAUUUGACACUGGAUAUGGCACUGGGAAAGAAGAAAAACGUGGAGCCAUUUACCAGUGUUCUUAGUUUGCCAUACCCAUUUGCUUCCGAAAUCAAUAAAGUUGCUGUAUUUACAGAGAAUGCAUCAGAGGUCAAAAUAGCGGAAGAAAAUGGAGCUGCAUUUGCAGGAGGCACUAGUCUGAUACAGAAGAUUUGGGAUGAUGAAAUUGUUGCAGACUUUUACGUAGCUGUUCCAGAAAUAAUGCCUGAACUUAAUCGAUUAAGGAAGAAACUGAAUAAAAAAUAUCCAAAGCUUUCUCGAAAUUCCAUUGGCCGUGACAUCCCCAAAAUGCUUGAAUUAUUUAAAAAUGGACAUGAAAUUAAGGUAGAUGAAGAAAGGGAGAACUUUCUCCAGACCAAAAUAGCAACAUUGGAUAUGUCAAGUGACCAGAUAGCUGCCAAUCUGCAAGCAGUUAUUAAUGAAGUUUGUAGGCACAGACCGCUGAAUUUGGGUCCCUUUGUGGUACGUGCUUUCCUUCGUAGUUCAACAAGUGAAGGUUUAUUACUGAAGAUUGAUCCAUUGUUGCCUAAAGAAGUAAAAAAUGAAGAAAGUGAAAAAGAAGAUGCCUAAAUGUGGUGAAUUGUGAAAUUACUUUCAGUGGUUUAAGAAGCAAUGGAGAAAAUGAUAAUACAGCAUAAUUUUUACAUUUGAUGUCUUGUUAUUGAUCAUACUUGAAAGUGAACUUUAACAUUGAAAAAUCGUACAGUCAUUUCAAGAAUAAGAAAAUAAAAUUUUCUCUUUGUCUGAA